GAGAAGUGCUCCUGCCCUGGAGAGAGGCUCAGCACAGAAGGAGGAAGGACAGCACAGCCUACAGCCGUGCUCAGGAAGUUUCUGGAUCCUAGGCUCAGCUCCACAGAGGAGAACACGCAGGCGCAGAGACCAUGGGGCCCCUCUCAGCCCCUCCCUGCACACAGCACAUCACCUGGAAGGGGCUCCUGCUCACAGCAUCACUUUUAAACUUCUGGAACCUGCCUAUCACUGCUCAAGUCACGAUUGAAGCCCUGCCACCCAAAGUUUCCGAGGGGAAGGAUGUUCUUCUACUUGUCCACAAUUUGCCUCAGAAUCUUGCUGGCUACAUCUGGUACAAAGGACAACUGAUGGACCUCUACCAUUACAUUACAUCAUAUGUAGUAGACGGUCAAAUAAAUAUAUAUGGGCCUGCAUACACUGGACGAGAAACAGUAUAUUCCAAUGCAUCCCUGCUGAUCCAGAAUGUCACCCGGGAAGACGCAGGAUCCUACACCUUACACAUCAUAAAGCGAGGUGAUAGGACUAGAGGAGUAACUGGAUAUUUCACCUUCAACUUAUACCUGAAGCUGCCCAAGCCCUACAUCACCAUCAACAACUCAAAACCCAGGGAGAAUAAGGAUGUCUUAGCCUUCACCUGUGAACCUAAGAGUGAGAACUACACCUACAUUUGGUGGCUAAAUGGUCAGAGCCUCCCGGUCAGUCCCAGGGUAAAGCGACCCAUUGAAAACAGGAUCCUCAUUCUACCCAGUGUCACGAGAAAUGAAACAGGACCCUAUGAAUGUGAAAUACGGGACCGAGAUGGUGGCAUGCGCAGUGACCCAGUCACCCUGAAUGUCCUCUAUGGUCCAGACCUCCCCAGCAUUUACCCUUCAUUCACCUAUUACCGUUCAGGAGAAAACCUCUACUUGUCCUGCUUCGCGGAAUCUAACCCACCGGCAGAGUAUUUUUGGACAAUUAAUGGGAAGUUUCAGCAAUCAGGACAAAAGCUCUCUAUCCCCCAAAUUACUACAAAGCAUAGAGGGCUCUAUACUUGCUCUGUUCGUAACUCAGCUACUGGCAAGGAAAGCUCCAAAUCCAUGACAGUCGAAGUCUCUGCUCCUUCAGGAAUAGGACGUCUUCCUCUCCUUAAUCCAAUAUAGCAGCCGUGAAGUCAUUUCUGUAUUUCAGGAAGACUGGCAGACAGUUGCUUUGAUUCUUCCUCAAACUACUUACAAUCACCUACAGUCCAAAAUUGCUUUUUCUUCAAGGAGAUUUAUGGAAAAGACUCUGACAAGGACUCUUGAAUACAAGUUCCUGAUAACUUCAAGAUCAUACCACUGGACUAAGAACUUUCAAAAUUUUAAUGAACAGGCUGAUACCUUCAUGAAAUUCUAGACAAAGAAGAAAAAAACUCCAUGUUAUUGGACUAAAUAAUCAAAAGCAUAAUGUUUUCAUAAUUUUCUAUUUGAAAAUGUGCUGAUUCUUUGAAUGUUUUAUUCUCCAGAUUUAUGAACUUUUUUUCUUGAGCAAUUGGUAAAGUAUACUUUUGUAAACAAAAAUUGAAACAUUUGCUUUUGCUCUCUAUCUGAGUGCCCCAGAAUUGGGAAACUAUUCAUGAGUAUUCAUAUGUUUAUGGUAAUAAAGUUAUCUGCACAAGUUCA